AGAAACCCUCCUCCCCUCCCAGCCUCAGGUGCCUGCUUCAGAAAAUGAAGUAGUAAGUCUGCUGGCCUCCGCCAUCUUAGUAAAGUAACAGUCCCAUGAAACAAAGAUGCAGUCGGGCACUCACUGGAGAGUUCUGGGCCUCUGCCUCUUAUCAGUUGGCGUUUGGGGGCAAGAUGGUAAUGAAGAAAUGGGUGGUAUUACACAGACACCAUAUAAAGUCUCCAUCUCUGGAACCACAGUAAUAUUGACAUGCCCUCAGUAUCCUGGAUCUGAAAUACUAUGGCAACACAAUGAUAAAAACAUAGGCGGUGAUGAGGAUGAUAAAAACAUAGGCAGUGAUGAGGAUCACCUGUCACUGAAGGAAUUUUCAGAAUUGGAGCAAAGUGGUUAUUAUGUCUGCUACCCCAGAGGAAGCAAACCAGAAGAUGCGAACUUUUAUCUCUACCUGAGGGCAAGAGUGUGUGAGAACUGCAUGGAGAUGGAUGUGAUGUCGGUGGCCACAAUUGUCAUAGUGGACAUCUGCAUCACUGGGGGCUUGCUGCUGCUGGUUUACUACUGGAGCAAGAAUAGAAAGGCCAAGGCCAAGCCUGUGACACGAGGAGCGGGUGCUGGCGGCAGGCAAAGGGGACAAAACAAGGAGAGGCCACCACCUGUUCCCAACCCAGACUAUGAGCCCAUCCGGAAAGGCCAGCGGGACCUGUAUUCUGGCCUGAAUCAGAGACGCAUCUGACCCUCUGGAGAACACUGCCUCCCGCUGGCCCAGGUCUCCUCUCCAGUCCCCCUGCGACUCCCUGUUUCCUGGGCUAGUCUUGGACCCCACGAGAGAGAAUCGUUCCUCAGCCUCAUGGUGAACUCGCGCCCUCCAGCCUGAUCCCCCGCUCCCUCCUCCCUGCCUUCUCUGCUGGUACCCAGUCCUAAAAUAUUGCUGCUUCCUCUUCCUUUGAAGCAUCAUCAGUAGUCACACCCUCACAGCUGGCCUGCCCUCUUGCCAGGAUAUUUAUUUGUGCUAUUCACUCCCUUCCCUUUGGAUGUAACUUCUCCGUUCAGUUCCCUCCUUUUCUUGCAUGUAAGUUGUCCCCCAUCCCAAAGUAUUCCAUCUACUUUUCUAUCGCCGUCCCCUUUUGCAGCCCUCUCUGGGGAUGGACUGGGUAAAUGUUGACAGAGGCCCUGCCCCGUUCACAGAUCCUGGCCCUGAGCCAGCCCUGUGCUCCUCCCUCCCCCAACACUCCCUACCAACCCCCUAAUCCCCUACUCCCUCCACCCCCCCUCCACUGUAGGCCACUGGAUGGUCAUUUGCAUCUCCGUAAAUGUGCUCUGCUCCUCAGCUGAGAGAGAAAAAAAUAAACUGUAUUUGGCUGCAA